ACUGGUGCGCGAUUUAGGUCCGGAGGAGGCGUUGUGAGGUGAGCUUUUUCAGAAGCGCGAUCCCAGGACACGUCGGGAAGCAAGCAUCCCCAGGUCUGGAUCACUGUAAACAUUACAUUCAAAUGGGGAGGUGAGGGCCAGAAGUCCCCACUUCUGGGGUCGGAUUUGUUCCGGGACCUGCAGCCGGAAGUGACUCCAAGCCUUGCAGCGUGAUGGGAGAGGAAAGAGGCGCGUUCCUAGCCGCGGGACUGGGUGACCCGCCUCUCCCCCAAAUUGUAAAUCUUGUAUAAAGGGAACAAAGAUCCCACUUGCCAGAACUGUGAAAAUUGAGGCAGAUGGUAUAGUGUCUAGCGCAGUAGAUAGAAGAUUCUCAAUAAAGUUGCUUCUUAUUUCUACAGGUCUCUCCAAACUACUGCAGUGCCCUAGUUUGCGUUUGCUCUGCCACCGAAUUAGUCUUUACUAAUUAUUGCCAAAUUACCCCCACUUCUAUACACUUAGGGCUGCUGUUCUCGACUAAAUGUUUGGAGUGAAGUCUUGGAUGAAUUUACACACACCAGGCCAUACCUAUGCAUGUUUUUAAAGGGACGCUGACUUACCAAAAUAAAAUACUGCACCUCUUCUGUAAAAGACAGAAGUGAAGUUAUUCUGGAAGCUUAGGGGGUGAAUAUGGUUGGACACAAAUCAAGACAGCUGAAAGACAGCAAGUAGCUAGGCUGUCCUGUCUGAAUAUCUUGGACUUUAUGUUUGUCCAGGUGGUAGUGGUGGUGGUUGCUGUUGUUCUUCUGUUUGUUUUUAUAGUUGAUUUUCUUCUCCCACUUUGGAACCCUUAAGAGCUGCUUGGAAAGAGGACCAAAGACGUCUAAAAAGUCAUUUGGAAAUAUCUCUAAAUAUUUGUUACCAUGUAUAAGCUGCUAAAGAGAAAUUGGGCCCAACAAAACUAAUUGAAUAAUUGAGGCAGAUUUGUGUGUAUCAUCAAAUUCUAUCCAGAAGUUGAAGAAUCUGAAUUUAAAGAUUGUGUGCAUUUAAUAAGAGGAUGACCUUUCAGUUUAAUUUCACUAUAGAAGACCAUCUGGAAAAUGAAUUAACACCCAUUAGAGAUGGAGCUUUGACCCUGGAUUCCUCAAAAGAGCUGUCAGUCUCAGAAAGUCAAAAAGGAGAAGAGAGGGACAGAAAAUGUUCUGCAGAACAAUUUGACUUGCCUCAGGAUCACUUGUGGGAACAUAAGUCAAUGGAAAAUGCAGCUCCCUCUCAAGACACAGACAGUCCACUCAGUGCAGCCAGCAGUUCAAGGAACUUGGAGCCACAUGGAAAACAGCCCUCCUUGAGAGCUGCCAAAGAGCAUGCUAUGCCUAAAGAUUUAAAGAAGAUGUUAGAAAAUAAAGUCAUAGAAACAUUACCAGGUUUCCAGCAUGUUAAGUUAUCAGUAGUGAAAACCAUCUUGUUGAAAGAGAACUUCCCUGGAGAAAACAUAGUUUCAAAAAGCUUUUCUUCUCACUCUGAUCUGAUUACAGGUGUUUAUGAGGGAGGCUUAAAAAUCUGGGAAUGUACCUUUGACCUCCUGGCUUAUUUCACAAAGGCCAAAGUGAAAUUUGCUGGGAAAAAAGUCUUGGAUCUUGGUUGUGGAUCAGGUUUACUAGGUAUAACUGCAUUCAAGGGAGGGUCCAAAGAAAUUCACUUUCAAGAUUAUAACAGUAUGGUGAUUGAUGAAGUAACCUUACCUAAUGUAGUAGCUAACUCCACUUUGGAAGAUGAAGAAAAUGAUGUAAAUGAGCCAGAUGUGAAAAGAUGCAGGAAACCAAAAGUAACACAACUAUAUAAAUGCCGAUUUUUUUCUGGUGAGUGGUCUGAGUUUUGUAAGCUUGUACUAAGUAGUGAAAAACUUUUUGUAAAAUAUGAUCUCAUUCUCACCUCAGAAACCAUUUACAACCCAGAUUAUUAUAGUAAUUUGCACCAGACUUUCCUUAGACUGUUAAGUAAAAAUGGACGUGUACUUUUGGCCAGCAAAGCACAUUAUUUUGGUGUAGGUGGAGGUGUUCAUCUCUUUCAGAAGUUUGUAGAAGAAAGAGAUGUUUUUAAGACCAGAAUACUCAAAAUAAUUGAUGAAGGAUUGAAGAGGUUCAUAAUUGAAAUAACUUUUAAGUUUCCUGGUUAAUUAACAUUCACUGAGUAUCCAAAAUGAAAUAAACAGAAGGACCAAAAA